AGAGGCUGCGGCCUACAGCCGGGGAGAGGCCAGCCCGGCCUACAGUGCGGACACAGGACAGAGGGGAGCCAGGUGAGCCAGGUUUUUGGGCAGGGAGGGACUGGGAGACCCCAGAGGAGAGGGCUGCCCCCAUGAUGACCCUGUCCGCAGCUCCGAGAGACCCUGAGCAAGGCUUUCUUCACUGGGCACCUCCUGCAAAUCAGGCCCUGCACUAAGUGUUAGGGUCACGGCAUGACAGUGACAAAGAUCCCGGCCCUCUUGCAGUUUCUGUGUUAGUAGCAGGGAGAUGGAAGUAAACAAAAACAUAUGAAAUGAGUAAAUGAUCUCAAAUGUCAGAAGGGGAUAAGUGAAAAGAGAAAAAGGAGAGCAGAGUGAGGAGGACAGGGAAUGCCGGGGGAGGGGGCUUGGGGUUUUAAAGAGGGUGGCCUCUUUAAGGUUAAAUGAGGUUCAAUGCAAAAAGCCCUAGUGACAUUUGAAGAAAGGGUGUUCUGGGCAGAUGGAGAUGCCCUAGCAAAUGCUGGCAGUGGCAGGGAGGCCUGGAGCAUUCAGAACAGCAAGGAGGCAGUGGCAGCAGAGCAAGGAAAAGAGGUAAGGCAGGACGAGAGGAGCCGCACUAGGGGCACUUGCAGGACUCCGGGGGGCAGAGGAUGGGGCCCCUUGCCAGCACCCCCACAGCCCUGCUGGGGGUAUUGGUUUGAAAGCCUCAUAUGAAUCAUUUGCUACAUGUGGUUGCAUGACCCUUAUAAAGUCUCCUCCCUUUCCAAGGCCCACAUCCUCUCCAUAAAAUGGUAAUAACAGCAGUGCAUCUGUCAGGUUGAGGUCAGGAAGGAAGGGGAUCAAAAGCAUGGCAGCCUGCCGGAGAGAUUUACAACAUACCUGCUGCAAGCUAGGAAAUGCAGAGCUGGCCUCCCAGGCCUUGUGGGAGGAACAUGCAGUUCCUCUUGCACACAGGUUCUUUGCACUGACCAAUGCUGAGAGCAGACCCUCGGAGCAGCCGGGUUGGAAGUGUCUCUCCAUAGUCACCAGACAGAUCCAGGAUAGGAUGGGCAGCCCAGUGCACCGAGUGUCAUUGGGGGAUACCUGGAGCAGGCAAAUGCACCCCGACAUAGAGAGCGAGAGGUAUAUGCAGUCCUUUGACGUGGAACGGCUCACCAACAUCCUUGAUGGAGGUGCCCAGAACACUGCACUCCGCAGGAAAGUUGAGAGCAUCAUCCACAGUUACCCGGAGUUUAGCUGUAAGGACAAUUAUUUCAUGACCCAGAAUGAGCGUUAUAAGGCUGCCAUGCGGAGGGCAUUCCACAUCCGGUUGAUAGCUCGGCGCCUGGGUUGGUUAGAAGAUGGUCGUGAAUUAGGCUACGCUUACAGAGCCCUUUCUGGAGACGUGGCCUUAAAUAUACACAGAGUCUUCGUGAGAGCCCUCAGGAGCCUGGGCUCAGAGGAGCAGAUUGCCAAAUGGGACCCACUCUGCAAAAACAUCCAGAUCAUCGCAACGUAUGCACAGACAGAGUUGGGACAUGGGACAUAUCUUCAGGGCCUGGAGACUGAAGCCACCUAUGACGCAGCCACCCAGGAGUUUGUGAUACACAGCCCCACGCUGACUGCCACCAAAUGGUGGCCUGGAGACUUGGGACGGUCAGCCACCCAUGCCCUGGUCCAGGCCCAGCUGAUCUGCUCAGGAGCCAGGCGGGGCAUGCACGCUUUUAUUGUGCCAAUCCGGAGUCUUCAGGACCACACCCCACUGCCAGGAAUCAUCAUUGGGGACAUCGGACCCAAGAUGGACUUUGAUCAAACAGACAAUGGCUUCCUGCAGCUGAACCAUGUGCGGGUCCCCAGGGAGAACAUGCUGAGUCGCUUUGCACAGGUCUUGCCAGAUGGCACCUACGUCAAACUCGGUACAGCACAGAGCAACUACCUUCCCAUGGUGGUGGUGCGGGUGGAGCUGCUGUCAGGGGAGAUCCUCCCUAUACUGCAGAAGGCCUGUGUCAUCGCCAUGCGCUACUCGGUCAUCCGCCGCCAAUCCCGGCUCCGGCCCAGUGACCCAGAGGCAAAGGUCCUGGACUACCAGACACAACAGCAGAAACUCUUUCCUCAGCUGGCCAUCAGUUAUGCCUUCCAUUUCCUGGCAGUCAGCCUCUUGGAGUUCUUCCAGCACUCCUACACUGCCAUUCUGAACCAAGACUUCAGCUUCCUGCCUGAGCUCCACGCACUGAGCACGGGCAUGAAGGCCAUGAUGUCAGAAUUCUGCACCCAGGGAGCUGAGAUGUGCCGCAGGGCCUGUGGCGGACAUGGCUACUCAAAGCUGAGUGGCCUGCCAUCACUGGUCACCAAAUUGUCGGCCUCCUGUACCUACGAGGGUGAGAACACAGUGCUCUACCUGCAGGUGGCCAGGUUCCUGGUGAAGAGCUACCUGCAGACUCAGAUGUCCCCUGGCUCCACGCCACAGAGAUCUCUCUCUCCAUCUGUCGCAUAUCUCACCGCACCUGACCUGGCCAGGUGUCCAGCCCAGAGGGCAGCCGACUUCCUCUGCCCGGAGCUCUACACCACGGCCUGGGCACAUGUGGCAGUAAGGCUCAUAAAGGACUCAGUGCAGCAUUUACAGACCCUGACGCAAUCCGGAGCUGACCAGCACGAGGCUUGGAACCAGACCACUGUCAUACACCUCCAGGCUGCUAAGGUGCACUGCUACUAUGUCACUGUGAAGGGUUUUACAGAAGCUCUGGAGAAACUAGAAAAUGAACCAGCGAUUCAGCAGGUGCUCAAGCGCCUCUGUGACCUCCAUGCCAUACAUGGAAUCUUGACUAACUCGGGUGACUUUCUCCAUGACGCCUUCCUGUCUGGUGCCCAAGUGGACAUGGCAAGAACAGCCUACCUGGACCUGCUCCGCCUGAUCCGGAAGGAUGCCAUCCUGUUAACUGAUGCUUUUGACUUCACCGAUCAGUGUUUAAAUUCAGCACUUGGCUGUUAUGAUGGAAACGUCUACGAACGCCUGUUCCAGUGGGCUCAGAAGUCACCAACCAAUACUCAGGAGAACCCUGCCUAUGAGGAAUAUAUAAGACCACUUUUACAAAGUUGGAGAUCCAAGCUAUGAAAUAACCAACAGUAUUCAAGAAGCAACCAGCACCAUCAUGUGAUAAUGGUACUAUGGCAUAUAUGCAACAUUAAAAUUUUAAAUUAGA